GUGGCGUCGUGUUUUGCUUGCUCUGUGAGCGUGGUCCAGGUUCGACGCCUUUUGCGCCUUAGAGGCAUCAGCGUAUCAGUUUCCUCGUAAGUCGGGAGUGAUGGAACGACCACCCUGUAGUGCGGCUGUGAGAAUUGAGAUGAGGCUUGGUUCAUAUUGAGUGCUCAGCUUUCCUGGCUUAUAGACAGUGGAGGGGCGUGGCCCCACCAUGCACCCCAAGGGUCUCAGACUCAAGGGCCAGCAGGAGGAGUUGGCGGGGAGCCUUGGGCCCCUCUGGCCUCAGCCGGAUUUCCCAGCCAAACGCAGAGAGAGAUGCCCUGGACCAUCUUGCUCUUUGCAGCUGGCUCCUUGGCGAUCCCAGCACCAUCCAUCCGGCUGGUGCCCCCGUACCCAAGCAGCCAAGAGGACCCCAUCCACAUCGCAUGCAUGGCCCCUGGGAACUUCCCGGGGGCGAAUUUCACACUGUAUCGAGGGGGGCAGGUGGUCCAGCUCCUGCAGGCCCCCACGGACCAGCGCGGGGUGACAUUUAACCUGAGCGGCGGCAGCAGCAAGGCUCCAGGGGGACCCUUCCACUGCCAGUAUGGAGUGUUAGGUGAGCUCAACCAGUCCCAGCUGUCAGACCUCAGCGAGCCCGUGAACGUCUCCUUCCCAGUGCCCACUUGGAUCUUGGUGCUCUCCCUGAGCCUGGCUGGUGCCCUCUUCCUCCUUGCUGGGCUGGUGGCUGUUGCCCUGGUGGUCAGAAAAGUUAAACUCAGAAAUUUACAGAAGAAAAGAGAUCGAGAAUCCUGCUGGGCCCAGAUUAACUUCGACAGCACAGACAUGUCCUUCGAUAACUCCCUGUUUACCGUCUCCGCGAAAACGAUGCCAGAAGAAGACCCGGCCACCUUGGAUGAUCACUCAGGCACCACUGCCACCCCCAGCAACUCCAGGACCCGGAAGAGGCCCACUUCCACGUCCUCCUCGCCUGAGACCCCCGAAUUCAGCACUUUCCGGGCCUGCCAGUGAGGCUGAGGACUGGGGGACCCCUCUGUCUCCAGGCAUUCGGGGGCCUGAGGUCCCUCCAGCUACUUCUGGGGGGGCUCUGUCAGCCACUUUCUCAGGGAAUUGGACAGAGGAAAGGAAGGGGAACCCUGGCCUUGGGAUUUUCAUCACAGAGGAGUGGGAGAGGGGACACAGGCAUGGGCCUGGCACUAUACAGACAACAGGAAGUUCCCCUCUCGACCUUCGGCUCCUCAGGACCACCAGAGAAGGAGAUGUCAGGACCCCUUCUUGUCCCCCAGCUGGGCCAUAAGACGUCCCAGGUCUCUGCACACCCGUGGAAUUCCUCCCUUCCCCAGUGGGUUUUUGAGCAUAGGGUGCCCUUGGGUGUGUUGUGUGUCUGCCUGCUGGCUUGCUUAAGUUAUUAAUUAUAACACGGGUCAAGGUGUU